AGUGCUAUCUGCAGGCUGGCCAGCUUCCUCUGCGCUCCGGAAAGCUGCGGCCCAGCGCGGACUAGUGAGGACCUCCACAGCUCCUGACAUUGCCAGGAGUCCUGUCGGCGUUUUCUCCCAGCCUCCGCCAUGCCGGCGGUGCUGGGUUUUGAAGGCAGCGCCAAUAAGAUUGGCGUGGGCGUGGUGCGGGAUGGCAAGGUGCUGGCGAACCCGCGGCGGACUUACGUCACGCCUCCUGGCACAGGAUUCCUUCCAGGUGAUACAGCCAGGCAUCACCGAGCUGUUAUCCUAGACCUGCUGCAGGAGGCACUAACAGAGUCUGGAUUAACCUCCCAGGAUAUCGACUGCAUUGCAUACACCAAGGGCCCUGGCAUGGGUGCCCCACUGGUUUCUGUGGCUGUUGUGGCCCGUACUGUGGCCCAACUGUGGAAUAAGCCAUUGGUGGGUGUGAACCACUGUAUAGGCCACAUUGAGAUGGGCCGCCUCAUCACUGGAGCCACCAGCCCAACCGUGUUGUAUGUGAGUGGAGGAAAUACGCAGGUGAUUGCAUACUCGGAACAUCGUUACCGUAUCUUUGGGGAAACCAUCGAUAUUGCAGUGGGUAAUUGUCUGGAUCGUUUUGCUCGAGUGCUGAAGAUUUCUAACGACCCAAGUCCAGGAUACAACAUUGAACAGAUGGCAAAGCGAGGCAAGAAGCUAGUUGAGCUGCCAUACACUGUAAAGGGGAUGGACGUCUCAUUCUCAGGGAUCCUGUCUUUCAUUGAGGAUGUAGCCCAUCGGAUGCUGGCCACAGGCGAGUGUACUCCUGAGGAUCUGUGUUUCUCCCUGCAGGAAACUGUGUUUGCAAUGCUGGUAGAGAUCACAGAGCGAGCCAUGGCACAUUGUGGCUCCCAGGAGGCCCUCAUUGUGGGAGGAGUGGGGUGUAAUGUGAGGCUACAGGAGAUGAUGGCAACAAUGUGCCAGGAACGUGGAGCCCGGCUUUUUGCUACAGAUGAGAGAUUCUGUAUUGACAAUGGAGCGAUGAUAGCCCAGGCUGGCUGGGAGAUGUUUCGGGCUGGACACAGGACCCCACUCAGUGAUUCUGGGGUUACACAGAGGUAUCGGACAGAUGAAGUAGAGGUGACCUGGAGGGACUAAUAAGAUCAACAGAAUCAGAGUAGAUAGUUCCUUAAUCGGAACCCAAAGGACCCCGUGCCUCAAUCUCUAUCCUGAUGUCAUGGGAGUCCUAGCAAAGCUAUAGACUCCAAGCAAGGCUUGGGGUCCUUUAUGGAACCCCAGGAUGACUCAGCAAUAAAAUAUUUUUGGUUUUUUGGUUUUGUAUGUUGGUGAUUGGAUUGUGUUGUUCAGGACCAAUGUAGAUUUGGUGCUGGAUAAAUUCUUGUUGGAGCUUGCUGCUGUGGAACCAAGAAUGAGGUAUCUUUUUUUUUUUUUUUAAGAAACGGAAUCUUGCUGUGUUUCCCAGGCUGGUCUCGAACUGGGCUCAAGCAGUCUUACCACCUCAGCCUCCUGAGUAAGGAUGCCAUUGUGCCUGGCAACAAUAGUAGUAUCAUAACUAUUAUUAUAGCAUCGGGUCCCGUGCUAACUGCUUUACAUUCAUUCUCUCAUUUAAAUUCUUUGAAGUAGGUGUGCAAGACUUCUCUCAAAAUAGCCUGGAGGCUCACACCUGUUAUCCCAGUGCUGUGGGAGGCCAAGUCAGGAGGAUCCCUUGAGCCCAGGAGUUUGAGCCCAGCCUGGGCAAAUAGCAAGACACCAUCUAUUUGAAAAAUGUAAAAAUUAUCUGGGCAUGGUGGCGCACAUCUGUAGUCCCAGCUCCAAGGGAGGCUGAGGCGGGAAGAUAGCUUGAGCCCAGGAGUUUGAGGUUGCAGUGAGCUGUGAUUGAGCCACUGCAUUCCAGCCUGAGUGACAGAACAAAACCUUGUCUCUUAAAAACAAACAAACAAACAGCCUGGAGAUUGGUCUAACUUGUAACUCUAAAA